UCUGAGUAGGAGCAGAGACACAUCAUUGCCUGCCUCGCGCCCUGCCCUGCAGCUGCAAUCAGCCUAUGUCCACAUGGGUUCACUGCUUCUGUUGUGGAAACCGCAUUGGAAGGGCAGCGGCCUUGGUGUUAGAAGAUUCCAGUCUGUGUCCUGGUGCUGCCCCGGCCCUGGGCCUGCAGCUCCCAAGCACAGAGGCAUGAGUGGGGAGAAUGUCACCAGGGUCGGCACCUUCAUCCUGGUGGGCUUCCCCACGGCCCCAGGGCUGCAGUACCUGCUCUUCCUCCUCUUCCUGCUCACCUACCUCUUUGUCCUGGUGGAGAACCUGGCCAUCAUCCUCACCGUCUGGAGCAGCACCUCCCUCCACAGGCCCAUGUACUACUUUCUGAGCUCCAUGUCUUUCCUAGAGAUCUGGUACGUGUCUGACAUCACCCCCAAGAUGCUGGAGGGCUUCCUCCUCCAGCAGAAACGCAUCUCUUUCGUCGGGUGCAUGACGCAGCUCUACUUCUUCAGCUCCCUGGUGUGCACCGAGUGUGUGCUUCUGGCCUCCAUGGCCUACGACCGCUACGUGGCCAUCUGCCACCCGCUGCGCUACCACGUCCUUGUGACCCCGGGGCUGUGCCUCCAGCUGGUGGGCUUCUCCUUUGUGAGUGGCUUCACCAUCUCCAUGAUCAAGGUCUGUUUUAUCUCCAGCGUCACGUUCUGUGGCUCCAACGUCUUGAACCACUUCUUCUGUGACAUUUCCCCCAUCCUCAAGCUGGCCUGCACGGACUUCUCCACUGCAGAGCUGGUGGAUUUCAUUCUGGCCUUCAUCAUCCUGGUGUUUCCACUCCUGGCCACCAUGCUGUCAUAUGCGCACAUCACCCUGGCUGUCCUGCGCAUCCCCUCGGCCACCGGCUGCUGGAGAGCCUUCUUCACCUGCGCCUCUCACCUCACCGUGGUCACCGUCUUCUAUACAGCCUUGCUUUUCAUGUAUGUCCGGCCCCAGGCCAUUGAUUCCCGGAGCUCCAACAAGCUCAUCUCUGUUUUGUACACAGUUAUCACCCCCAUCUUGAACCCCUUGAUAUACUGCCUGAGGAAUAAGGAAUUUAAGAAUGCCUUGAAAAAAGCCUUCGGCUUGACGAGCUGCGCCGUAGAGGGGAGGCUUUCUAGUCUUCUGGAACUUCAUCUCCAAAUACACAGCCAGCCUCUCUGAGGAGGCCAUUUGACUGUUUGCAUUAUUGUAGUACCGCAUUUAUUUAAAAAUUACUUCCAAAUCUAUUUUUCUCCUUCAGGAAAAAAACUGAGGUUGAGGUUAAUAGCAUAGGUAUUGUUGUUGGUGUUGUAAUACCAGUACUUUCUUGUUUUUGUAGAUGAGCAAAGCUGUAGUUAGUAAAGCUUAAUGAAUUUUCCUCGCCUUUAAAAUUACCAUGCACAUUUCAGAAAGCAGCAAAACAUGCCAGAUCAUCUGAGAUUUUAAAGUCCCCAAUAAAUUGCGGUGUGUUAAAGUACUAAAUAUUUAACCAUGUGGCAAAAUGAGCUCCAGGUGUCCCUGAAGCAAAAUGUGUCUGGGAAAAGUAAGGGCAUGUAGCCUUCUGUUUUAUACCCAACGAAUGUUCUCUGAUUGUCUUGGGUGGAUGCCCCCUCUGCCUUUUUCCUAAAUAAACCCCUACUGCAUGCCCAGUCAGCUGCUGAGAAAAUAAAAAUUGUUUUAUUAUUGCA